GAUUUGGAGAAUGCCUGCGCCGGUCCUAUUCUUUUUUCCUGGGGUUUCUGGAUUUUAGUCUUUUAAGUGGAUCCUCCCGUCGGAUUACUAGAAUCCUGCGCUCACUGCAUGCACACAGUUUCAAUUAAAGGGGGGGUGGGGGUACAAGGAGGGUCUCCAAAUGCGCGAAUCCUUCCCAGUGUGUCUUUCUUGUCUUUCUGUGGCUCCCUGGCCCUUCCGCCCCUGCUCCCCAUCCCGAGCCCCGCAUUCGCUUUGCGCCUGCUGCGCUUGAACUUGUUUCUGGUGGAGCGGAAGGCGCGAGCUGCGGACCCUCACGCAGAGAUUUGUUGGUGUUAACGCAUCUGACAUCAACUAUUCAGCAGGCCGCUAUGACCCCUCAGUUAAGCCUCCCUUUGACAUAGGUUUCGAAGGCAUUGGGGAGGUGGUGGCCCUAGGCCUCUCUGCUAGUGCCAGAUACACAGUUGGCCAAGCUGUGGCUUACAUGGCACCUGGUUCUUUUGCUGAGUACACAGUUGUGCCUGCCAGCAUUGCAACUCCAGUGCCCUCAGUGAAACCCGAGUAUCUUACCCUGCUGGUAAGUGGCACCACCGCAUACAUCAGCCUGAAAGAGCUCGGAGGACUGUCGGAAGGGAAAAAAGUUUUGGUGACAGCAGCAGCUGGGGGAACGGGCCAGUUUGCCAUGCAGCUUUCAAAGAAGGCAAAGUGCCAUGUAAUUGGAACCUGCUCUUCUGAUGAAAAGUCUGCUUUUCUGAAAUCUCUUGGCUGUGAUCGUCCUAUCAACUAUAAAACUGAACCCGUAGGUACCGUCCUUAAGCAGGAGUACCCUGAAGGUGUCGAUGUGGUCUAUGAAUCUGUUGGGGGAGCCAUGUUUGACUUGGCUGUAGACGCCCUGGCUACGAAAGGGCGCUUGAUAGUAAUAGGGUUUAUCUCUGGCUACCAAACUCCUACUGGCCUUUCGCCUGUGAAAGCAGGAACAUUGCCAGCCAAACUGCUCAAGAAAUCUGCCAGCGUACAGGGCUUCUUCCUGAACCAUUACCUUUCUAAGUAUCAAGCAGCCAUGAGCCACUUGCUCGAGAUGUGUGUGAGCGGAGACCUGGUUUGUGAGGUGGACCUUGGAGAUCUGUCUCCAGAGGGCAGGUUUACUGGCCUGGAGUCCAUAUUCCGUGCUGUCAAUUAUAUGUACAUGGGAAAAAACACUGGAAAAAUUGUAGUUGAAUUACCUCACUCUGUCAACAGUAAGCUGUAAAAACAGAACAAUGACAUAAAUCAAGGGAGAAAGAAAAUGGGCACUUUAUGUCUCAGAAUUACUCAAAUCAAUUUAUUUUUAGUUGGUAAUGGAUAUAAUAUUUCUUAAAACAAAAGUAAGGUGUUAAUGAAUAGGUCUCUCCUUCUCCUCCUCCUCCUCCUCUUCCCUUGGGGGAAAAAAAAAAAUGUGCUAAUAAAACUUCCCUCCAUGGCUAAGAGGGAAAACGCUUACAUUCAAUUCUUUAGUCAUGGAUGGUCUCGUUCCAGAUGUUAUUGUUCCAGGGAACUAAAUUCAUUCCUGAUGCCAGAUCUGAUCGAGUCAGUAUGUCUUCAGCUUGAUCAGAUUUUAAAAUCAGUUUUGAAAGUGGUUCCCGACUUCUUUGCUUUGGGAGAAUUUGGUCUUAUGCUCAUAAGCAGUUCAUGAGUGACAAGUGUAGCAAAAGCCAGCCAUAUAUUUUCAGAAUCUAUAUCCUCAGGAAAUGGUCCUUUUUUUUUCUAUAAAUCACCAACCAACUAUCUAAAUGGACAUUUGGGGGAAUUCCCUCCCAAAUUUGAUUUUGUUAUUAGAAAAAUGAUUCCGUGAACACAGAUGUGUUUUGAAGAAGUAGCACGUAAUGGCUUUUAUCUACCAUCAACCUGAUAAGGCACAUGUGAAAUGGAAAUGUUCUCUUUCCUCUGAAGCAGCAAAUUAAUGUUGAAAACUUACAUAGACAGAAAGUAGGUUUUGGAAAGGGAAACCACAGAGAUUAGGGGGACUUAAAAUUAAUAUAGGCACAGGAAAGAGAAAAGUGUGCGCUCCAUUCUCAGUGGGGGUUCACCACAAAACACGGGCCCCAGGAGGGAAGCGCUGUCUAGGCACACGGCAAGGCCUUAGUAACAGCAUGCUACACUGCUCGAGGUACGGUAUGUCCCAUCGCCCUGUGCACCGUAGAGACCUCAGUCAUCUCAAGGAAGAAUACAUUUGCUUCUCCUUAGAGGCGUUCGAACUAGAAGCUAUGCGUUACCUCUGAUUCUGGAAACAGAAUAGCAGCCACUCAUUCUGCAUUCCCAUUUUUCUCUCCACGUGUUCUGGUGGAAUGAGAUGCUCCUUGGCACUAUAGCCUGAUGUCCCACAUUGACCCACUGACCACACAGGAAAAGCAGCGAAACCUGCACCCUCUCUUCUGAGUCACGCCUGUGGCUCAUCGGCUUCCCUCUUAACCUUUAGUGCCCUGAAGACUGCUGCCGCUGUCACCGUUGCGCUGAAACCCCAUGGGCCCGUUCUGAUUGAAGGUGAAGCCCACCAGAUUAUUUUUCAAAGUCUUAGGUUUCGGUGUAUCUAACCUGCUCAGUAAAUAUGGACGCAAUUAAAGAUGCUCUAGGAAAUUUGGGGACUGUAUUUAAUUUUUCUUUCCUUCCAUCUGAGGAGCAAGGAAAUCCUACUGCUGAAUAGCUGUUAGUAUCUAUUUUACAAGAUUUACUCAUUUUCAGGUACCUAAUGUAGCUGCUAGCAUGCAUGCACAACAAUACAAUUUAUAUGGUAAAUGGAACCAAAUAAUGGCUUCACUGAAUGUUAUGGCUGCACUGAAGGGAAAUGUCACGGUAAAUAGCUGCCAAAUUAUGGAUCAUGCCGAAGUGUCACAACUGCACUAAAGACAAAUAGCACUAGAGGCUAUUGCCACUGUGACGCUUUUGAGUUAUGAAGAAGGGUAGCGGCCUGAUGCGAGGCUCUUUGUGUCCUCAUUAUAGCAAAGGGUUACUGGUGCAGGGGACUAGGAAAAACCCGUCCAGUGUGGUGCUUAGUUAUUCAUCCAUCCCUUUCAGACCUAACAGCCACAGCCACACGGAAAGAGACUUUGCCUCACUUUUACAUUCACAAACAAACAAAGGAGGGGGGAGCAGGUUUUAUGAAUGUAACUGUGCACAGGAAAUGACUGGUAAUGGAAAAAAUGUUGUAAUAAAAUAAUCUAAUCAAAGAAUAUUAUUAAAUUUAACAUAGUCUAUGUCCAAAAGGCUUAGUUGCUUCUUAUGCAGAUAGAUGUGUGAAAUCUAAGCAGUAAUGUACUUUCUCCCUUUGUAAAGACUUGGGGAGUAAGGACAUUACCAACUAAAUUGCUUCUUCGAAACUGAAGUGAGUCCCGGUUUGUUUCAUUUUAAUGGGAGGGUAAUAAAGAUGAAAGACCAACAUUUUAACUGAUGGAUCCCUUAAGCUACAGAAUAGAAAUUUAUUGUGUUUUGAGGGAAUAUACUAAAUGCAGCUAUGUAAAAAUAAAAUUCAAACGCCCAGGAUUAAAAUAAAAUAUAAUCUGAAAACCUCAUGUUCUCUCUUUCCCCAAACUAAGAAAGUGCACUGCAUGCUGUUUUCACUUAUUCUUAGAAAACAAGCAUGAAAGAUUCCGCCCAUUCAGAUAAUGCCAAAAAUAUGUUUAAACUUUUUUUUAUUCUUUUGAAAAAUGAUUUGUAAAUUGAGGGUCAUAGUUCAGCAUCAGUUUCAUCUUCUGGGAUUAUUGUUCAAGACCAGCCUCUAAUGGGAGGUGAAACGGUACGAUGGUCUCAACACCUUUCUUCUGAACUGUAAUACAUAUCACAAAAAGUACAUCCAUAAUUCAGGGCAAUUGUCAGUCUUUUUAGAGAAGGGGCCAGGGUGGAACAAUCCCAGUGAGUAAAUUAUUUCUCAGCGUGGACUUCUCUGCAUGUCGGGCUUAAGGUCACCAGCCGGGCAGGGUGGAAGGAGCUUGCCUCUUUGAGAAACCAAGGAGUCCCAGUGAUCUGUUACCAUUUGGUUAUGACUUCUAAAGAGCCAAAUGCUAUUCCUUCAAGCCUGUUUUGCAGGCAGAAAAUACCAGCAGUGUCAUUUAGGGGUUCCUUUGAUGAUGACUACUGCUGUUAACUGACCUCAGCAUUAAAAAAAAAAAAAUUCAGGGAAUAGUUUGCAAAGAAAUGAAGGAAGUUUUGCAUGAUAUAUUCUAUAACUUGUCAUUAUAUGAUUUCAUCUGGAUGAAGUUCCUCAGGAGUAGGAUAGAGCCUCUGUAAAUGGUCAUUAGUAUUACAUUCUGUGUUUAUCUAAUGAAAGUGCAGUGACAAGUAGCUGCUUCUUAUUAAAAUGAAAAUCCUGCAUUAUGUACUUGAGGAACAUUCCAGCUAAUGAGGAUGUAAUGUCCUCAGUACAACGCAGACCUUCUUUUUGUGUUCACCACCACAAGAUGCUGGAAGCUUGACAAAUGAUAUCAUUUAAGACACAUGCCUGCCUUAGGGACCUGGUUUUUGGCUUCCUGUUUCUGGCUUUUAUUUGGGUAACGUUUAUAAUGGCCACCCGACUUGUACCUGGGUAAUGUUUUAACCCCUUCCCCAGAGUUCUCAAUUAGCAUGAAUUUACUACAGUCAGAGUUUCCUUUAAAUUGGGGUGGGGGUGCUAAGCACUGAAAAUAUCUUUCUUGAUUACUUUACCAUGUGGACAUAUGGGAUAAAUACUGUAUUUCAGAUUUACAUAAAAGUAGAUUAGUAAUGCACAGCUUUCAGAAUAAAAACUGAUAAAAAAGACCAAGCACUAUCAACUUUGGACAGUAAUUUCCUAGGUGUUAAACAAGUUUUCUGAAUACAAUCUGGAUGCAAAACGGCCUGAUUUGAUGAAUUCAUAAUUUUCUUCUGUAUACUUUCAUUUUAUUAAAUAUUUUAUUACUUGGUUAAACACAAGAAUUAUCUAUGUAAACUUCAUGGGCUUUUUUGUUGAAAGUUAGAUGUUCAGUAACUAAUUUCCCAGUUAUGGCCCAGAAUUAAACAUUUAUGAUCAUAUUUCAGAAGUCAAAAUACAAAACUGGAUUAUCAAAACGGUUGGUGUGGUCACUUUAAACUGGACUAUCAGUAUGGUUGCCGUGGUCACUUUAAGCGGGAUUAUCAGUACGGUUGGUGUGGUCACUUUGGUUUAUCAUCAAUACAGUUGGUGUGGUCACUUUAAACUGGAUUACCAAUAUGGUUGGUGUGGUCGCUUUAAAGUUUGUUUUCAUUUUUUUUCUAUUUUUAAUUCUUACGGGUAUAUAGAAGGUGUAUAUAUUUAUGGGGUACAUGAGAUGUCUUGAAACAGGCAUGCAAUGUGAAAUAAAUAAGCACAUCAUGGAGAAUGGGGUGUCUACCUCCUCAAGCAUUUAUCCAUUGAGUUGCAAACAAUCCAGCUACACUCAGUUAUUUAAAAAUGUACAGUUAUUAUUGCUUAUAGUCACCCUGUUUGCUAUCAAAUAGUAGGUCUUACUCUAUUUUUUUCAUUUUAAACUUUGAAUUUUAUUUUUCCUAGGCUUAUAGCAUCAUGCUAUCCCCCUUGUAAAAGGAGGAAUGCUUGGCAUGAGAACCUUACUGCUGUUACCAUGAACAAACUAUGGAAUGUUGGCAAAAGAAAAAAAAAAGUUACACAAAACACACAAAUAACAUUUUAAUAAUAUGUAUCAGAUCAAGUGAUUCUUAGUAGUAGUUGAUAUUCACAGGAAGUCAAAAAAGGACCUAUUUCAAUUAUGUCUGCUUGAAUCCUGUUUAAUUGUUUCCCUGGCUGAGUAGCUAGUGUGACACAGCAGCAAGACUAAAGGGGCUCUGUGGUCCACAUUGUCCUCGAGUCUAUUCUUGCCCAUUAUAGACCUGCCCAUUGGUGCUCACUCACUGCAUCCCAGGAGGCUUGACUGUCCUCAGGAAGCAUGUUGGGGUGCCCUUAAGGGUAAGUAUCCCGGGGAGCACAGUUUGGAGAAAACCAAUACGUCUUCAUGUAUGUUGAGAAGCGCUGGGCCAAAGUACAGACUUUUUUUUUUUUUUUUUUUUUUUUUGGGACAAGACCUCGGCUCUGUCACCCAGGCUGGAGUGCAGUGGUGCAAUCAUGGUUGAUUGCAACCUCAACCUCCCUGGUUCAAGCCAUCCUCCCACCUCAGUCUCCUGAGUAGCUGGGACUACAGGUGCACAUCACCAUGCCCGGCUAAUUUUUUUGUAUUUUUUUACUAGAGAUGAGGUUCUACUAUGUAGCCCAGGCUGCUCUGGAACUCCUGGGCUCAAGCAAUCCUCCCACCUCGGCCUCCCAAAGUGCUGGGAUUGCAGGCAUGAGCCACCAUACUGGCCUAAGUGCAGAAAUUUGAACAUGUGCCUCCACCCCAAGCCAAAAUUUCCCUUGAGGAGCACUAUCUAUCUGAUGAUGUCUUUGAAACGGUAUGAAAUUAAAAUAAUUAAAACAUCCUGCACAUAGGUGGUAGCAUCUAAUAUGAAAGAUGGAUUUAUGCUUAGAGCUCAGAAAAAUCCUCAUAAAAUUAUUGUGUCUUAUCCUCGGCACCUAAAGAACUGAACAGGGUCUUAGAAUGAUCAAAUGGAUGGUUUGUUUGGUUGGUGGGAGAUGUUGAAACGUGGGUAAGGAAUGGUGUCCUUAGAAGAGAGGUUGCCCUAGAUGCCGAAACCCUGGAGGUCCAUGGUUGCCAGCAGAAACUUACAGCUGGGAGGAGCCUGCACCCAUCUCUGGCUCUUGUGAAUGAGAAGACUCAAUUUGUGUUUUUGUUUUUUUGAGAAAGGGUCUUGCUCUGUCACCCAGACUGAAGUACAGUAGCGUGAUCUCAGUUCACUGCAGCCUUGACCUCCUGGGCCCAAGCGAUCCUCCCACCUCAGCCUCCUGAGUAGUUAAGACUUCAGGUAUGCAUUACCAUGCCUGGCUAAUGUUUUUUUAUUUUUUGUAGAGACAAGGUCUCCCUCGUUGCCCAGGCUGGUCUCAAACUCUUGGGCUCAAGUGACUUUCCUGCCUCGGCCAUCCAAAGUGCUGGGAUUACAGGCAUAAGCCACCGCAACAUGCCCCAGUUGCUUUUAAACUGUUAAAUGUGGGAUUUAAAGAAUAAUCUAGUUCUACCCAUUUUAUGAAUGAAGAAAAGAAACUGGGACCCAGAGAGAAAAGGUGCCCGGUCCAAGGUUACAGAGCCCGUUGGACUCAGAAGUGAAGCUGGAACACUGGCCAAUGCCCUCCCAUCCGCCAGGUGACUUCUCUGCAGUCCCCUUUACCAUCUGCCCGGGUCCUUUGGGAUACGGCUGACUAGGGGUUUGAAGAACAGCAAUUGGCCUUUGUUAUGAAUCUUUUUGUGGAGAUAAACCCAGUAGAAGUAUCACGGUUCUGACCAUGAAAGUGUGUUCAACUCUAAUCCAGCACAAUUAGGAUUCCAGAUCAUUUGAUUCUGUGUCGUCUAAAUAUCACAGAAAGUUAAAAACAAAUUAGCCUCAAUGGAAUUAAUGGCUUAAUAUCCAUAAUUUAGUUUUAAUGCUAGGAGGAAGGGCUCCUGUGAAUGUGUUCUUACAAAUCAAAUAAAGAAAAUCAAAUAGAGAAAA